AGAGCGGAUGUGAGGGGCGCCGAUGGCGGAGGGAACGGCGGAGGCUCCUCUAGAGAAUGGUGGUGGUGGCGACUCGGGAGCCGGAGCUUUGGAACGAGGAGUGGCGCCCAUUAAGCGUCAAUACCUCACCACCAAGGAGCAGUUUCACCAAUUCCUGGAAGCCAAAGGGCAGGAGAAGACUUGCCGGGAAACCGAGGUAGGAGACCCUGCUGGCAAUGAGCUGGCUGAGCCUGAGGCUAAGCGGAUCCGACUGGAGGAUGGACAGACGGCGGACGGGCAGACGGAGGAGGCAGCAGAGCCCGGGGAGCAGCUACAGACUCAGAAGAGGGCCCGGGGACAAAACAAGGGCCGGCCCCAUGUGAAGCCCACGAACUACGACAAGAACAGGCUGUGUCCCUCCCUAAUCCAGGAGUCGGCUGCUAAGUGUUUCUUCGGUGAUCGCUGCCGCUUUCUGCACGACGUGGGGCGCUACCUGGAGACCAAGCCGGCCGACCUGGGCCCCCGCUGCGUGCUCUUCGAGACCUUCGGCCGGUGCCCCUACGGCGUGACCUGCCGCUUCGCUGGGGCCCACCUGAGGCCCGAGGGACAGAACCUGGUGCAGGAGGAGUUGGCGGCCCGCGGGACCCAGCCCCCGUCCAUCCGCAACGGCCUGGACAAAGCCCUGCAGCAGCAGCUGCGGAAGCGCGAGGUCCGCUUCGAGCGAGCUGAGCAGGCCCUGCGCCGGUUCAGCCAGGGCCCCACACCCGCUGCCGCUGUCCCCGAGGGCACGGCAGCCGAGGGCGCUCCCAGGCAGGAAAACUGUGGUGCCCAGCAGGUCCCCGCAGGGCCGGGCACUAGCACCCCUCCCAGCAGCCCCGUGCGGACCUGCGGGCCCCUGACGGAUGAGGACGUGGUCAGGCUGCGGCCCUGUGAGAAGAAGCGGCUGGACAUCCGUGGCAAACUUUACCUGGCCCCCCUCACCACGUGUGGGAACCUGCCCUUCCGACGGAUCUGCAAGCGCUUCGGGGCGGAUGUGACAUGUGGAGAGAUGGCCGUCUGCACCAACCUGCUGCAGGGCCAGAUGUCCGAGUGGGCCCUACUCAAACGCCACCAGUGUGAGGACAUCUUUGGCGUCCAGCUGGAGGGCGCCUUCCCCGACACCAUGACCAAGUGUGCCGAGCUGCUGAGCCGCACCGUGGAGGUGGACUUUGUGGACAUCAACGUCGGCUGCCCCAUCGACCUCGUGUACAAGAAGGGUGGGGGCUGUGCCCUCAUGAAUCGCUCCACCAAGUUCCAGCAGAUCGUCCGUGGCAUGAACCAGGUGCUGGAUGUGCCGCUGACUGUGAAGAUCCGCACAGGCGUCCAGGAGCGUGUGAACCUGGCGCACCGCCUGCUGCCCGAGCUGCGGGACUGGGGCGUGGCACUCGUCACGCUCCACGGCCGCUCUCGGGAGCAGCGCUACACCAAGCUAGCCGACUGGCAGUACAUCGAGGAGUGCGUGCAGGCCGCCAGCCCCAUGCCCCUGUUCGGAAAUGGGGACAUCUUGUCAUUUGAGGAUGCCAACCGCGCCAUGCAGACUGGUGUCACCGGGAUCAUGAUUGCCCGUGGCGCCCUGCUCAAGCCGUGGCUCUUCACGGAGAUCAAGGAGCAGCGGCACUGGGACAUCUCGUCGUCCGAGCGCCUGGACAUCCUGCGGGACUUCACCAACUACGGCCUGGAGCACUGGGGCUCGGACACGCAGGGCGUGGAGAAGACCCGGCGCUUUCUGCUCGAGUGGCUGUCCUUCCUGUGCCGGUACGUGCCCGUGGGGCUGCUGGAGCGGCUCCCACAGAGGAUCAACGAGCGGCCGCCCUACUACCUGGGCCGCGACUACCUGGAGACGCUGAUGGCCAGCCAGAAGGCAGCCGACUGGAUCCGCAUCAGCGAGAUGCUCCUUGGGCCAGUGCCCCCCAGCUUCGCCUUCUUGCCGAAGCACAAGGCCAACGCGUACAAGUAGCCUCAGGCUUUCCCAGGGGCACCCUGGGGCGAGGAGAGUACAAUAAAUUUUAUUCUUUUAAAA